ACCCUCAGCAGAGACAGACCCCAGAUCUGGGCCCAGGACUUUGUGCAGGGAGGGGAAAUGCAGACUGGACUCUGAAAUGGGCACGUACAGAGACGAAGAGACCCCAACAUGCUUCAGGCUUUGAGUGGAGAGGACACAGCCUCUGCUGGGACAGGGAACAGAGGGAUGUGGAGUCCCUGAAGAUGCUUUUGGACAAUGGUCUGAGGUUGGGACAGUGGCAGGAGAUACCAUUCACCCAGGAUCUCCAGGACAAGAGAUCAGCCUGGCAGUUACAUGUGUUUUUUUUUCAAACUGGUUGCCAGGUUGGCAUGAACGAUGACAUCAGAGAUUCCGACCUUCCUGAUUGGAGGGACCGGACUCCGUGGUGCCUGGAGAUCAGUUGGACAACAGUAUCUUCUCAGAGCUGUUCUCCACUCCUGACUUCUCCUAGGCUUGAGAAUUGAUAACAUACUCUUCUGGAUCCUAGCAGUGUCCAGAAGAAGGCCAUGGACAGAACGGAGACUAGGUUCCGUAAGAGGGGACAGAUUACGGGAAAGAUCACGACCAGCCGUCAACCGCACCGCCAGAAUGAGCAGAGUCCCCAGCGGAGCACCUCGGGGUACCCCCUCCAGGAGGUGGUGGAUGAUGAAGUGUUGGGACCAUCAGCCCCUGGGGUAGAUCCCAGCCCCCCAUGUAGGUCCCUUGGCUGGAAAAGGAAGAGGGAGUGGUCAGAUGAAUCUGAGGAGGAGCCGGAGAAGGAGCUCGCCCCUGAGCCUGAGGAGACCUGGGUAGUGGAGACGCUGUGUGGGCUCAAGAUGAAGCUGAAGCAACAGCGAGUGUCACCCAUCCUCCUUGAGCACCACAAGGACUUCAACAGUCAGCUUGCCCCUGGGGUAGAUCCCAGCCCCCCGCAUAGGUCCUUUUGCUGGAAAAGGAAGAUGGAGUGGUGGGACAAAUCUGAGGAGUCGGAGGAGGAGCCACGGAAGGUGCUCGCCCCUGAGCCUGAGGAGAUCUGGGUGGCGGAGAUGCUGUGUGGCCUCAAGAUGAAGCUGAAGCGACGGCGAGUGUCGCUCGUGCUCCCUGAGCACCACGAGGCCUUCAACAGGCUGCUUGAGGAUCCUGUCAUUAAAAGAUUCCUGGCCUGGGACAAAGAUCUGAGGGUGUCGGACAAGUAUCUCCUUGCUAUGGUCAUAGCGUAUUUCAGCCGAGCCGGCUUCCCCUCCUGGCAAUACCAACGCCUUCAUUUCUUCCUGGCUCUCUACCUGGCCAAUGACAUGGAGGAGGACGACGAGGACUCCAAACAAAACAUCUUCCACUUCCUGUAUGGGAAGAACCGCUCUCGCAUACCCUUGCUCCGUAAGCGUCGGUUCCAGUUAUACCGUUCCAUGAACCCGAGGGCCAGGAAGAACCGCUCUCACAUACCCUUGGUCCGUAAGCGUCGGUUCCAGUUACGCCGUUGCAUGAACCCGAGGGCCAGGAAGAACCGCUCUCAGAUAGUCCUGUUCCAGAAACGUCGGUUCCACUUCUUCUGUUCCAUGAGCUGCAGGGCUUGGGUUUCCCCAGAGGAGUUGGAGGAGAUCCAGGCUUAUGACCCAGAGCACUGGGUGUGGGCGCGAGAUCGCGCUCGCCUUUCCUAGAGCUCCAGGGACCGUGGAGGCCUGAGGUCAUCGGCCUGAGAGAAGAACACCGGACCCAGGGGAGAUGUGGAUUUUCAGCAGGAACUUUAUUCCAAUGCUAAUGGCAGACACCAGGAAGGAGGAGAGGAACCAUUUGUGCAGAUCAUCUAGAAGAACCUGGACCAUUCUUGAUGGAGCUGAAUACAGUGAUCACGUUGUCCUCCUAGGAGCAGGGGUGGGGGGAGGGGGAUGGGGUCCUUCUAGGAGUCCUUGGAGAAAAGUAAGAAACCAGGAGUGUUUCCAGUUCCACCCUUUCCUGGGGCACCACCACCCUUUUUAUAUUGCUGAAUUCCAACCUCCCUGGGGCGGAACCUGGAGGUCCUGUUUCUUACGGACUUGGUUGCCACAGUCCAGGAGCAUUUGAAGGCACAAUGCAGGGGCUCAGAUUGGCACAGAAUUCUUUUGUGAAAUAUCAGUGCCACAGAUUGUAACAGAUAGCUUCAUGCACACUCUGCAUUUUAUUGGUUUGUUUGGAAAAUGUUGGCCAUUGAAUUAUUCAUAGAUUUAUUUCAAAUAGUUUGGAAAUUGUUGUACUUUUGAAAACAUGCUGUUCCUGUAGUUUUUUGAUGAGAGUUAUAGUUGUUAUAUAUACAUAAAGAUAAUUUUCUUUUCAUUUUUGAGACAAUUCUUUUUAUCCUAAAUAUUUUAUCAUCUUUAAAUUUGUUUCUGUAUUAUUAUAUGUGCUCCUGAAGCGAGCACUCUUUUUAUCUAUGAUACUUCCAUAAUAAUCUCUUCUAUUUAUAGCUAUUGGUAGUUCCCCUAAAUUCUGACGAUAGAAAUUUUUAUUUGCUGUUUAGGUUUGUGACUGAAUUGUGAGAAUUCAGUUGUGAUUUUUAACAUGUGUCAGAUAUAUAUACUAACACGUCUAAUAUAUACUAUUUUAUUGGUUUAUUUUGAAAAACAUGGGUAUAGAAUUAUUUAAAUAUUAUUUUAUUUAUUUAAAUAUUUAUUAAAUAUAUUUAUUUAUUUAAAUGUUAUUAUUACUUUAAAUAUUAUUUUAAAUAUUUUGGAAAUACUGGUAUUUUUGAAUAGAUGCUGUUUCUAUAAAGCUGUGUGAUGGUAUUAUAACUGUUAUAUACACAUACAUAUAAUUUUGUUUUCCUUUUUAAGAGAGGAUUCUUUUCAUCCUAAAUCUUUUACCUUUCAAUCUUUGUAUCUAUUAUUACACGUGCUGCUGAAGGGAGCAUGGUUUUUAUCUAUGAUACUUAGUUAACAUAUAUAUUACAUUUAUAGCUAUGUAGUAGUUCCCCUAAAUUCUUGUAAAAAUAAAUUUUUAUUUGAUAUUUCAUCUAUGUUUGAAAUGUGAGAAUUCAGAUGUAAUUUUUUACCUUGAUUUGGCAUGUUUGUAUGUUACUUUAAAGAGGAUGUGUGUUCUAAAGGAGGACAUGAGCUGUGUGUUUUCAAGAGAACAAUAGAGUGUGUCUCUUGGGGAAACGUAAUAAAAAUGAACUUUUCUCACCUUCA